ACAUUUAGUUUCAACACUUCUCCUUUCAGAGCUCUCUCUCAGGACUAUUCUGGCUUCUCAGGAUCCAUUGCCCUUGCCCAGGAGAGAGAGCCUCGCUGGGACCCAGAAACCGCGAAAGAAGAUUCGACCUACCUGUGGAACCAGACACAACUUGGUCCCCAAAGGUCGCUUAGGCGACCCCACUGCAAACGGCAAGUCAACUUGUGCACUUAAAACGUAUCAGUUUAUGGAAUGCUUGUUUAAAGUCCUCAUUGGACAUGGUAUAGAUUAUGGGGUUGAUGAGGGAGUUGAGAUAGCCCAGCCAUGUGAAGAAGUCAAAGAUGGCUAGGUGGAACCAGCAGGCAUCUUUGCAGAUAGGCAUCACUAGGGAGAUGAUGAAGAAGGGUAGCCAACACACAAUAAAGGCUCCCAAAAUGAUCCCUAGGGUCUUGGUGGCUUUGCGCUCCCUAGCGGCCAUGAGUUUCUUCUUUUCCAGCAGGGCGUCGGAGACUCGCACUUUGACUUGGUUCACAUACACAGGAGAUCCGGAUUCGCUGGGCACGUCGGGAACCCGCGAGUUAAUAGAGCCUGACGCCAGAAGAAGGGCGGCAGCGAGAUAGAGAUGGAGAAGACCCACACCAGCGCGAUCAUGACCGCCGCCCUCUUGGGAGUCCUUUUAGCUGAGUACUCCACGGCGUCCGUGAUGGCCCAGUAGCGGUCCAGGGCGAUGACACAGAGGUGCAGGAUGGAGGCAGUGCAACAAGUGAUGUCCGACGACAGCCAGAAGUCACAGACCACCUGGCCCAGUGUCCAGCGGCCGGUGACAGUGUACAUGGUGCUGAUGGGCAUCACCAGGAUGGACACAAGCAGGUCGGUGACCGCCAGAGAGGCGAUCAGGUAGUUAGCCGGGGUGUGCAGUUUCCGGGUCCGGUACACUGUGGCAAUCACAAAGGCAUUGGAGAGCGUGGUGGCCAAGGUGAUGAGCGCCAAUAGCAUAACCAGCAGUACUUUCCAGGGUAGGGAGAUGGAGUCCUGGUAAAUGUAGUCCUUGGCGCUGCAGUUUUGGGAGGGAGCAGAGGAUAAGUUGGCUUGAGGAACCCAGGUCUCGGAGCCCGCGGGCGGCGGUGGAGCGCACUGAGCACCCGGUUCCUCCAUGGCUCUCCUCGCCCCAGCUCCGGAGCGCAGCUCUUGGGCAUGGAGCGGACGAAGGAGAGGGCGGAAGGACCGUGGCGAUCGCAGGUUUGUCCCCAGUUGAUAGUUCCGUGAGUUCCUCAAUUAUUCCUCCGCCCAGGUUCACAGCUGAAACUAGAGGUCAUGGGUGCGGCAGCCAAGGCAGGCGGGCGCCUCCCCUGCACUUCCAGAGCGCCUAGCUAAGCCGCCGCGUCUGUGGUUGUUCCUCUCCACACCGGGUCUUAGACCUGGGUUGCUAAGAGCUGGCCCACCGAGCCCUGCUCCGCUCCAGCUCCCUGGAGGCGUCUAGUGCAGGAGGGUGAAGUACUGCUUGAGGAGAAGGCUUUGACCAAAUGGGAUCUCUUACCCCAGUUGCUUGAGGCUGAGCGUCUCCUAACCUGGACGCUUUUGGAUCUGCAGACUUUGCCCACAGGAGUUUCCUAGGUGUAGAGACCAAAGCUUGCAGGCCAGCGAGAGGUCCCGAGAUCUUGCAUUCCCACCCCUCGCCCCAAGCUGGGGCACUUUUGGGGGGCUGCAGCGGCCGCCAGAGCUGGGUGGGGUGAAGUCUAGGAGCAGCGCUGCGCCGCGCCUCGCGCCGGAGCUCUGCCCUCCCUCUCUUUUCACUCUCUGGCCACUCGGACGAGCUGCCCCGCGGAGACGGAGCCAUAAAAGGGGGGACACGGGGGCUGGAGUUGCGGCUGCUCGGGCCGCGCCGCCGCCACCGCCACCCUGGUCCCACGGGAGCCACUCGGAGCCAUGCCACUGGGUGCGCGGGUCUGGAGGACCUGGCGCGGCACACUGGGAAGGGGCAGGUGUCUGGGGGAGCUGGAGGGACGCGGCGUGCACCAGCCCGGGAGAAGCGUGCGAGCUACGGAGCAGAUGGGCUCUUUAUAUAGAGUCCAGGUCCGGUCCGCCAGAGCAGUGCAACUCGUGCGGCGCGGCGGGUGCGGACGCCCGCUCCCCAUCACCUUCCCUUUUUCUCUCUCCCUCCCUCUUUUCCCCCCGCCCUGUUCCUUUCCUGGCCAAGGAAGCUCCCGCCGGGUCCUACCGCCCUAUCUCCCCGCUUCCCACCCUGGGCCAUCCUCCCAGCCCUGACAACCUGGAGCUGCAUUUCUGGUCAGGGGAAGAAGGCGUCCUGUUCUCGCCUCUACGGACAUCAGAGCUUGCUGCGCUGACCUCCAGUGAGACCCAUGUCCUUAGCCAUGGUCACAGGUUUAGUCCAGCAGUCUGGCCCUAGGCUCCUGCCUACCACUCCCACCCUAGGAGGCCAGUGUUAGGCGGGGAAGCCCUGGUCUCUGACCUCUCCGCUCUAAAAUCAUAUCCAGCCCUGAUGGCCACACCCAGGUUAGGAGGCACCAGUAAUAUCGCUGUAGAGGGCCCAAUGUUUGCAUUUUGUACUUUGCCGUCCUUAACUCUUGAUACAAUAAAAACUAUUUUUUCAUCUAGUUUUAGAAAUUUGUGUUUUUCACUCAACUAUGAGUCAACAGGGAAAAAGACAAGCUAUCUGCGAAAAUGUAAAAGUUAUCACAAACAGAAGCCAACUGUAUGUGAAAUUAAACCUUCUGCUCCACCAUCCUCUUCCAGCUGCUCAGUGCUUCAGUGCCUCUGGAAAACAGUUGCCAGUAAGCGUGUUCCUUCCAACAGCCUACCUAGAAAGGAGGUCAUCAGAAUUCAAGAAAAAAGGGGGAUGGUGGGGCGGGGAGGACUGGAACCAUCAUCAGCACCAUCUUGUGUGUCUCCUUUGCCUUCAACUAAUAUGUGGGAAUGUCAGCCAUAAGCUGCAGCAUGCAAUACCAGUACCUAGGUCUCAUGACCAGGGACGGAUCCCCUGUCCUCAGUUUCUCCUCUGACCUCAACAGAAACAAAUGUAGGGUAGAGAUGCAAAUCAGAAAGUAUGAAGAAAAGCUCCAGGAAAGGACAAGGUAUUUUCAGCUCGAAGGAUUAAAUGAUCCCCACUACGAAUUCCUAGAGCCUAGAUCCAUGUUUGGCACCUAGAGUGUAUCUAAUAAAAACUGCAUUGUAAAUGAAUUCAUCUGUUUAAGCGCACAUAUAUUUUAAAGAGAAUCAUUCUGUGUCAGAACCUAAGGCUAUCUGAUCUGAUCCCUCCACCCAGUUUUAGAGGAAGAGUAAUUGAGAUCCUUUGAAAGAAGAGCUUUUUACCCAAGGCAAUAAAGCACAAACCCAAGUUCCCUUAAUUCCCGGUUCUCUAAACCAGGCAAGCAGGCAAAAAAUAGAGUGCCUACUCUAUGCUGAGUAUUUUUCUAGGCAUCCGAGGUAUGGAGGCCAGUGGGAGUAGACUCAGACCCUCUUUUCCAGCAGUUUACAUUCUAGAAGAGACAGACAAUAACUACAUGAACAAGUAAAUAAUUAAUACUUAUACUUUUCUGUAGUGUUAAGUGUUUUGAAGAAAAACACACAUACACACAUGCAUGCAUUGAGAGUGAGGGUACUCCUUUAACUAAGGUGGCAGCUCUUCAAGGACGUCCUCUAGAUGCGGUCUGGGCUGCAGCAGCCACCCUGAGGAUAAAAGCACAGCCUUCUCUCUUUUUCUCCUCCAGUCCUAGCACCUAGCAUUUUGCCACCAACCUUAAGCCUCAUUUUCACCACAUUUUAAGGGAUCCUUCCCAUUCUCCCACCCCAUCCACCUAGAUAAACAAUUAUUUUUGUCAACUGCAGCGCUCACUUAGAAACCAUAGAAGAGGGAAGCAAAGCCGGCGAGUUUAAACCGCUAGGUGGGGGCAUUGGCCAGGACGGAUCAAAAGUGUGUGCGAUUGCGGGUGUGUCCUGUGGGAGUGCGGGGUGCCAGGAAACAAUUUUCCCGUUAUCCUAGGAGAACUGGAAACGAUUAGAGACAAGUGUUAAAGGGAUGGGAAGCGGGGGAAGGCCGACAGGAAUGUAACCAGCUCCAUGCGACCUUUCCUCUUUUAAUUUCUGCUCGGGAGCAUGGGACGGAGAAAAAACAAAGCAAAAUUUGUUCCCCACACGGUUUUUGGCUUUAGCGGUUUGGGGACCUGUGGCUUUCUCCAGCCAUGCCUCCACUGCUUCGCAGAGUCCCAGACUCCCAGAGGAAUCCGCCCCUUGUAGGCAGUUUGAUUUUACCCUCUUUGGUAAAGAGCUGCUUAAACACACACCGCCAUCAUAUUGACCGGAUGUUGGCAGAGUUCAGUGAAGAACCCCAUUUCCUUAACCUGACUUCCGCAUUUCAAGUAUUCCUUUCUCACUUUAAAACACAUAAAACAUAGGUGUUUGCACAGAGGCGCAUGUGUGUGAAACACCCAAGAGAGAAAGAGACCCUGUAAAGUCGCCUGUGCCUGGGUCACCCCUUCGGAGUAGGGGUCGCUGGGUAAGGUCCAAGUGCCAGCUCUGCAGUCCCCAGCGGCGCUAGAAGGAACCUCCAGGCAAGUUUUGGGGGAAAUUCACCUGACAGGGGAGGAGCAGAGAGGGAAUCAGUAGCGGAAGGGAAAGGGUGGAGAUGGAUUACCUGAGCGCAGCAAAACUUAGUUGAGUAGAAAUAAGCUCCCGUAUGAACACCGGGCACUAAAACUGCGAAUUAAUGUGGUUCCCUUAUUAUCAAUUCCACGCACGUGUACGUUUGGCAGAAGCUGAGUAAGUGGAGAAUAACUCUGGAACUGAAAUGAAGUCAGUGAACCGACACAAAACCAGAUCCUAGCGGUGAGCUGGCUGCGGAGGAACCAAAGAAAAAUGAAUCCUCGAGGAACCCUCUCCCAUGCUAGGAAGAUGUAGUUCUACAGCUGCAGCACCAAAUUCGAGGCGCAGGCUGGGAAGUUUAAAGCGCAGCGCUAACCAGACUGGACACUGUCAAGGGAAGCAUACUCUGCCUACAGCAACCACAAGAGAUAUCUCACGGAAUUUAUUGCAACUCAACUCUAUGUAAGCUGGCAGUCAGCUAACCUUAGUCAGCCCUAGCCAGCUCUCUUGCCUGCGGCGACUGAGUCUUGCUUUCAGCAUCCCUAGAGUCUUCCAUCCAGAGAGUAACUAUUGAAAGAGGUCCAGGCCCAGGAGCAAAGAAAGUCCUGAUUUUAUCUUUGCUUUGCUGAAAGAAAAACGUUAGAACACUCAUGCGCCUGUCACUUUUCUCCUUUGAUACAGGAAAAUACAACCCCGCACUCACCAUCCCACUGCUUGAGAAAUCUGGUGUGGAGGCCUGUCUUGCUGCUUCUUUCAAAUUCUGCUUCCUCCAUCUAUGGCCAGCAUAUAUAUAUAUAUUUUCACUUCAGAAACGGGCAGCAGGAGACCACCAGCUCAUGUGUGCACCAUCCUAAUGUGUGCUGGCAGCCCAUUUCUAGGUUUAUCUUAUACUUCCUCCAGUAACUAUUCCUUAAAGAACUGACUGAUGGCAAUGAAACUAUCAGGUCCACCCAGUGACUUGGUUCUUACCAUCCUUUGUGACUUCCUUGAUGAAAACUAUGAAAAUGUUCAGAUAAAUGACCAUAUACAUACAUAGAUAUACAUGUAAUUUUUGCGGACAAAUUCUGAGGAUUUCCAAACCAUAUGAGGCCCAGAUCCCUUUCCAUAUUCAUUGGCCCUCACAUUAGGCCUUUGACCUGAUAUUUGUGUCAUGGUAUUUACAUUCCAUCUGUUUUAUUAGAAAUUUUGAGGUCUUUCUUACCAAAUAAUGAAGGCAGGUGCUUUAUUCCCUAAAUGUUAGUUUGGUGUAACUUAAUCCCUAAAAAUUGGUAAUUCUCCUAUGUGUCUAUAUAUGGAUACAAAUAUCAUGUAAGCCAUAUUUCUAUUUAAGGAAGAAUGCAAACAAAACUUAGAGCAAAUAUAUAUAACUUAGACAUUUUUAAUACCUAUCUCCAUAUGAAUAAACACUUUGCUACUUUGAACAGAUACUUGCAACAAGUAACUUACUACUGGUUCAAAGAUAGCCCAGAUCCAACUAGAAGAGCCAGCUCCCAAUUAAGAUCUAAUCACAUAUUUCCUGGCUGAAGACGUAGGUCUUCAAAAAAAAAUUCUAUUUUACAGCUACUAUUAAGUAAUGUAAGUAAGGUUACAUAGAGUAUGGUGUGCUGAAUUUUUUUUUUCUUGGACAGAGUGAGAUUUGGCAAUGAGAAAUAUCUGAAUGAAAAAACAAUGCCAAUAAAUCCACCAAACUUACAAACAACUUGCUUUUUUAAGUUGGCAGUGUAAUUAAGCAGCUCUGUUCAAGAUGAAGUCUCUCUUGAAAAACCAAACCAAACAAUUUGAUGGUGAAGUUAUCUUUCAGCCUAAGUGACGAAGCAAUAGAAAUGCAAAGUCUUUAUUUUCAAACAAAUAAAGAAAAGUCAAAACACUUAUUUUGCCGAAGAAAAGCAAAAUUCUUAAUUUCAAACAGGAAAAAUGACAUCACUCUCUGGUGCUUUAUUGCUUCUUUACCUGUCAUUCAUGAAUAAGAAUCAUUAUCCUUUAUUGAACACAAUAUACUAAGCCAUAUGCUAUGUAUUCUACAUACAUUCUUACACUUAUUUCUUAUAACACUGAGAGUUGUCAUUAUCAUUCUCAUUUUCGGGAUAAAGAAGUUGAGGCUUAGAGAAUUGAAGUAAUUUUGCCAAUGUCAGACAGCUGGUAAGUGAUAGAAUCAAUUUUCAAGUUCAAGUCUCUAAUUUCAAGUUACAACCAUUGACCAGUAUUCUACACUGGAUCGGCCAUGCAGCUCAGCGUAGCCACCCAUUUUGCUCACCUGACCAUGACUUCGUUUCCUUCUGCCUGUGAGAUGACGUCAUUGCUCAUAGCUAUUUAAGUCUCCAUAGUAAUAUUCGUUUAGACGCCUUCAAAUUUUUAUGUGGGGGUGAAGGUAGGGAUUGGAGGUUGGGGGUGAUUGUGGUAAAAAUCAGGUAGAAAACUGGGCACUGUGAUUAUGUGUAGCUAGCUAUCAUUUCAAAAGUACUGUUGAUAGGUGAUCAUAUACUACAUAGUUUGAUGUGCACAGCCCAAAUAGAAAUCAAGCUAAGCUGUUCCAGAUUAGUUUUGGCAUAAUUAUAUUCAGGGUGUGCUUUAAUUUUUGCUGUUAUCUUCCAUUCUUUUUUUUUCUCUCUUCCUUCUCAUUAUCUUUUUCUUUAUCAUUAACACUUUCCCUAGGCCCAUAAAUAUACACAUUGAAAUAAAUAAUUAAUUAAAGCUUUUUAAAAAUUGUAAGGAUGGAAUGUAUUAAAUACAGCGAUAUCCCCUGUUCUCCAUAUUUAACCAUGUUAGUUUGAAUAUCAGUUACAAAAAUAACCGAUACAAAUUAAAUUGCUUUUCUUUUUUCCUAGUGUGUUGAACUUAACUGACUUUUUCCCCUUAUGGAUCAGGAACUCAUCAAAGAUAAAAAGACCUAUCCCUGGUGAUACACUUAUUUGAAUAAAGUUAUUUAAAGAACAUAUUAGCCAAAAAUCCCUGGUGUAGCAUGUUCAGUUACUAAGAACAAGGCAAACACCAAAAAUGUAAGCAAAAACAAAUCUAAGUGCCAAUGUUCUAAAACUUUUGCACUUUAUGUAUGGCAGAGCUCCUCCUAGCCUCAUUCAGAUCUUAUUUCUUCUUGCCAAAUAUACAGUUCUAAUAUGUUUAGCUAUAUGUUUUCCAAGGCCCCUGAAGAUAUAAGAAAUGGAUGAGAAACUAUGUCAGAUAAGCAUGUUGAAUGCAGCAAGAUGCCACAUUUAUCAUCUUUAUUGCAAAUUGAGCCAGGAAAUCUAGAGUAAAGAUUAAGAAGCAAAAGCCUAAAAGAAUGACAAUAACAACAUUAUGAUUUGUGUUGACCUAUUUAAUAAUAUGAUAUAUUAACUAAGACUUUUAUUACAAGUGAUGGAAAACCAAUUUAAUCAACCUAAAAACAAAAGACAGGAAUUUAUUUCAAGGAGAUUGGGGCUCCCUAGAGUCAAAAAAGGAAUUGAACCACCAAGUUUUGGACAAAGUAGGAAUGCAGCUGCAUCUUGGGAAAAACCAGCAUUCUGGAACGCAAGCAGAACUCUUCUUUUUCUGUUGGUUGCUGUCUGCAGGUAGAUUUCUUUCAUCUAUUUCACUGUAGAUGGGCUUUUCUCAUGUUGUUAAAACAUAGCCAUUAACACCUUUUGACUUUACAUCUUGCAGCUUCAAUUAUAUUUUAGAAACUAAUCUGAAUCAGAUCCACUUUAAGAAAUCCUCAGAAAUGGGUUCUGUUUCUGAGUAAAAUGCAGGAUGUCAUGAAAGGUGAACAUUACCAAAGUAACAACUGAAAAAGCUAUAAAUAUAAAAAAACCAUAUUUUAAAAACUUUGAAGAGUGUGGAAGCAAGAAUAAUUAGAUAAACUAAAAUUCUGCAAAAGGAAAUGUAUUUUUUAGGCUUCUCAUCCUCAGACUUUUUUCUGAAGGCAGAUGAAGCACCAAACCUCGGGUGAGCCAAUUAAGAACAAAUGGCGCAGUUACAGAAGACAGGAUGCAACCCUGCCACCUAUCUCUCUCUUUCAGAUGGUAAUCGUGUACCCAUACCACAGGACACUCCCCUUGGGUGCAUCUGCCAAACUGGGAAAAGUGUCCGUGUGCCUAAUUCUUCCUGGUUGUGUGACAAGACCUCGGACUGAGCUGAGCUAAGGAGCAGAAAAACUGCAACAAUAUGAGGGAAAAGACAGAAGGCAGACUGUGACAAAUGAAUUUAACUGUACUACAGAUGAAUUAGAUAACCACAAUGAAGAAGAUGGAAAGAAAGUUGAUGAUCUCCAUAACUUUAGAAAAUGCUUUGGCUUAAUAAUGCAAGGCUAAGGACAAAAAAUAAGUAUAUAUAGACAUAAACUUUAGUUGAUACAUUUGUUUCUCAGAGGGGAAGGAGCCAGAAAUUCUGAAACUACUUUAUUUGUAUAUUAGGGUUGAGCAAGCAAGUAAAUAUGUUAGAAUAUAAUGAGAACCAGGUUUCUCGCUGUCAAUGAAAGAAGCUACAAACAACAAAAAAAGGAAGGAUAAAAUGAACCGUGGUGUUGUAUAGGAGUUCUAGUUACCAAUGUGGAAUCGUGGUUUCUUUAAAACACAUCUAUCUACAUAAGUAGACAUAGAAACAAAUACAGAUGUGUAUAAGCAUGACUUUUUAUACAUAUGUAUUUUUUAUCUCUAUCUACUGAGAAAGCCAAAAGCAGCAGCACCCCAGUAGUCACAAAUAUCAGUGGCAUCCAGAUUUAGAUCUAUGAAUAUAAUUUUUCAAUUAAAAAGACAGGGCUCCUUGGAGGUCUACUUGACUCCAGGGUGAGGGUAAGAAAAAUUUAGGAGAAGUCUGAAGUAUCUGUGAUGACAGAAAAAAGAAAGCACUUAAAAAAUAAGGGAUAGAAGAGGGGAAACAAAGAAAAGAAUGGAGCAUAUAAAAAACACACAGGAACCAACCUAUCUGGGCACAAUGGUGUGCACCUGUAGUCCCAGGCACUUAGAAGGCUAAAGUGGGAAGAUCCCUUAAGCCCAGGAGUUCAAGCCCAGCUUGGGCAACAAAGCGAGACCCCAUCUCUUAAAAACAAAGAAGCCAAUAUGAAUGGUCAAAGUUGAAAAAUAUUGAAUAAGAAAAUAAAUAAUGAUAUUGUUAGAUUAUAAUGAAAAUAAUCAGAUAAUAUCCAUGAGCUUACACUAAUGCAAAUAAAUUAAUGGAUUAAUAAAAUAAAUAGAGGAAAAUACCAACUCUUCAGAAAAAAAUACAAUUAAUAAAGAUAGAAGGAAUGAUAGAAAUAUGAUAUUAUUACUAGAAUCUCAAAGGGAUAAUUGCUCCAGGUAAGAUCCAGCAGUGAAUGUUCAAAUUAGUGGAUAAAAAAAUAUUUUCCGAAACAGGAUAUUUGCAUAGUCUCUAAGUGCCUCUCUCAAAAUAAUUAGGAACCACAAAGAGAUAAAUAGUAAAUAUACCAUGGAGAGGCUAGCAGAUACAACCUUAGUCAAGUGAUCAAGGUGAGCCUCACCAGCAAUGACUUAUGUGAUAUGCCUCCUUCCCCUAUAUGAUAUUACCAAAGAGUACUUCACUUCUGUACUAUUCUUACCACAUAAUCCAUAACCACUGCCUGAACAUGGGAAAACAUCACACAAAUCAUUUGGUGGACACUCUACAAAAUAAAUAAUCAGUAUUCUUCCAAAUAUCAGCGUCAUGGAUAAGGGAGCCUAAGGAAUUGUCAUAGAGUACCUAAAACCAAAGAGACAUGUCACAUAAAUGCAAUGUGGGAUCCUGAACUGAAUUCUGAAACAAAGGAAAGGUCAUUAGUGAAAGACAGUAUUUUACCAAUGUUAAUUUCUUAGUUGUGAUCAAUAUUCCAUGUUAGAUGUUAAUGUAAGGGGAAACUAGGUAAGAGUAUAUAGGAAUUAUGUGUAGCAUUUUUGCAACUCUUCUGUAAUUCUGAAAUUAUUUCAAUUUUUAAAGGUUUUACCUAUGAAAGGGAUAAAGGAUUUAGGAUUAUGGGUCAGGGACAGCCAUUAGAUUUUUUUAAUGAAUACGUUUUGUGUAAUUAUGAUUUUUGAACUAUAUGAAGCUAUUAAUAAUUUAGAACUAAAUUUAAUGUUUUAAAAUAAAUACAAAUAAAAGGAGGUUUUUAAAAAAAUUUAUACUUUAGUUUCUAAAUUGUAUACAGGUUUUUCACAUGGAAUAUGAUAAAAUAAUAUGCACUAUUAGAAAGAAAAUAUGUAAAAAGUAUAACAAAAUUAAAAGAUUUAUGUAGAGUUGGUGGCAGAAAGUAUUCAAGCUUUGAGACCUCAUAACAUCAAAAUGAAGUUUCCAUUGCUAUUGUUUGUGAAGUACAAAAGUACAUUACCAGCUAUGUCAGAAAUAAUUUAGAGAUAAUAGGAAUACCCUGCCUUAAUUAAACUCUUAGUAAAUGUUCAAUGAAUGAGUCACUGUCAUGUUUCUCUGUCUCUUCUACAGACCUCAGUGGACUUGUUCCAAGGAAAAGGAAAGAGGGAUGGAGCAUGGUUUUAUGGCAGCCUUUCCCCAGAAUGAAAUAUACUUUGAGCACAUGAGCUCAUGAGCAGGAGAAAACUGAUCGGAAGGACAUGAUGGCCAUACAAACCUUGUCCUGCAAUAUUCUGCCAGCUUUUUCUCAAGAUGCAUAGAAACGUGAAGCAAGUGACAGCCACAUCACCAAUUUUAUCCAUAAUUACAAAAUGCAGCCCUAUUUCAGUGAUGUUCAAAGGUAACAAAGAAAAGUUUAUCUUAGACCUGAUAAAAUAUGAUAAAUUCAAUAUGCUUAACAGCUUGUAUGACAGGUCUGCUGAUGAUCAGCUUUGCCUGCAUAUUCAUUAUAGCUUGUGUUUACAUAGUUCAUUUUGUGUGAGGAUAUCAGAAUAUUUUUAAAAUAUUAAUAAUGCAUAGUCUAUUCAUAAAUAUUUAAAACCUAUAAGUGAUAUUAUGUUCAUCUCAGAAAUUUGGCAAAGAUUAAAAUUUCAUUGUUUAUCUACUAAGAGCCAGAAUGAAUAUUACUAAUCAAUAGAAUUUAAGAUUAAUUUGUGAAUAAAGUUUGUGAGUCUAAUUCUGGUAAUCUGACUGGAUAUGGUAAAUGAAAAAAAAUCAAAAUUAUAGCCAAAAGUUUAAAAACUAUAACAAAGGAAAAUAAAGCUGUUGUUGUAAAAACUAAUACAAUAGCACAAAGUUGGUUUUUUUAAAGAGAAAAAAUUUGAGAAAUGUUAGAUACAUUUAAAAAGUCGUGUAAGGGCAUGAAACUAAGGGGUCAAUGGAAGGAACUGUUUCAUGUGGGACAGCAUUCUAAAGCAAUCCAAAUGAUAAAACAAUUCAAGGAAGUAUUAAAAUAUCAAUAUGUAAGUACAUUCCAGAAAUAAGAAAAAGCAAUAAUGAUACAGAAUUUUGAAUCAGUAAUAGAAAGUACAAUAUUAAGAAUAUCAUGGAAUGUGGGGAAAGAGAAGCAAGUGAUUAAGUUGAAAGAGAUAAACAUGACAGAUACAUGGAGAAAGAAACAAGAAGACACAGAAUCACCAAUGAUAUUAAUAAAGAUGCUAUACUGCAUUGAGGAAAAUAUGUUUACUUACUGAAAAUGUUUACAAAUUCAAGACCAAUUAAUAAGAAAAGAUAUAUAUCAUAUAUAUCAUAUAUGUAUCAUAUAUAUCAAUCAUAUAUACCAUGUAUAUAUCAUAUAUAUCAUAUAUACCAUGUAUAUAUCAUAUAUAUCAUGUAUAUAUCAUGUAUAUCAUAUAUCAUGUAUAUAUCAUGUAUAUCAUAUAUCAUGUAUAUAUCAUGUAUAUCAUAUAUAUCAUGUAUAUAUCAUAUAUAUCAUAUAUAUCAUGUAUAUAUCAUAUAUAUCAUAUAUAUCAUGUAUGUAUCAUAUAUAUCAUAUAUAUGAUGUAUGUAUCAUAUAUAUCAUAUAUAUCAUGUAUGUAUCAUAUAUAUCAUAUAUAUCAUGUAUGUAUCAUAUAUAUCAUAUAUAUCAUAUAUAUCAUGUAUGUAUCAUAUAUAUCAUAUAUAUCAUAUAUAUCAUGUAUGUAUCAUAUAUAUCAUAUAUAUCAUGUAUGUAUCAUAUAUAUCAUAUAUAUCAUGUAUGUAUCAUAUAUAUCAUAUAUAUCAUGUAUAUAUCAUAUAUAUCAUAUAUAUCAUAUAUAUCAUGUAUAUAUCAUAUAUAUCAUAUAUAUCAUAUAUAUCAUGUAUAUAUCAUAUAUAUAUCAUAUAUAUCAUGUAUAUCAUGUAUAUAUCAUAUAUAUCAUGUAUAUCAUGUAUAUAUCAUAUAUAUCAUGUAUAUCAUGUAUAUAUCAUAUAUAUCAUAUAUAUCAUGUAUAUAUCAUAUAUAUCAUAUAUAUCAUGUCUAUAUCAUAUAUAUCAUAUAUAUCAUGUCUAUAUCAUAUAUAUCAUAUAUAUCAUGUCUAUAUCAUAUAUAUCAUAUAUAUCAUGUAUAUAUCAUAUAUAUCAUAUAUAUCAUGUAUAUAUCAUAUAUAUCAUGUAUAUCAUGUAUAUCAUGUAUAUAUCAUAUAUAUCAUGUAUAUCAUGUAUAUAUCAUAUAUAUCAUAUAUAUCAUGUAUAUAUCAUAUAUAUCAUGUAUAUAUCAUAUAUAUCAUCUAUAUAUCAUAUAUAUCAUCUAUAUAUCAUAUAUAUCAUAUAUAUCAUACAGCCUAUCAUGUUUGCUUGUUUUAUUUCCAGGAUAAUUUGAAAAAAUCUUAUAAAAACUGAUGCAGAAAAAAAUAAAAUAGAUUGCCUUUAACAAAGGGACUGAAGUCAGUUAAAUGUUUCUUUCAUCAGUACUCUAUUACCAGAUGAUGGAGAAAUGUUUGCUGAGUUUCAAGAAAAUAAAGGUUGCAAAAUCAGAUUCCUAUAUCUAGCCUAUUUGUUAUUUAGGUGUAAGGUAAACAGGAAGAUAGUCUUAGAUGUGCAAGAAUCUGUACAUUAAAAAAUACCAAAAUUCUAUUCAACUAAAAAGUUGGGAAGGAUGUGUGCUAACAGGUUUACCAUUGAUAUUCUUUGGGUGGAGGGAUUAUAGA